ACUCCGGCUCGGCGGCUCUGGGCCUGCGGCGGGCGCUGCGGGUUGGAGCUCGGGACGUGAUCGUGGGCGCGCAGCCAGCGGCUCCCUGCCCUUCCCCUCCGGGCCCUGAGUACCGGCCCCCCACCAAGGAGGAGCCCGAGGUCUCCGUCCCGGCGGCGAUGCUGCCCCGUCGGCCUCUGGCGUGGCCCGCGUGGCUGUUGCGGGGUGCUCCGGGAGCCGCGGGUUCUUGGGGUCGGCCGGUUGGCCCCCUGGCCCGCAGAGGCUGCUGCUCCGCCCCGGGGACCCCCGAGGUGCCGCUGACCCGGGAGCGCUACCCCGUGCGGCGCUUGCCGUUCUCCACGGUGUCUAAGCAGGACCUGGCCGCCUUUGAGCGCAUCGUGCCCGGCGGGGUCGUCACGGACCCGGAAGCGCUGCAGGCUCCCAACGUGGACUGGUUGCGGACGCUGCGAGGCUGUAGCAAGGUGCUGCUGAGGCCACGGACGUCGGAGGAGGUGUCCCACAUCCUCAGGCACUGCCACGAGAGGAACCUGGCCGUGAACCCACAGGGGGGCAACACAGGCAUGGUGGGUGGCAGCGUCCCCGUCUUUGACGAGAUCAUCCUCUCCACUGCCCGCAUGAACCGGGUCCUCAGCUUCCACAGCGUGUCUGGAAUUCUGGUUUGCCAGGCGGGCUGCGUCCUGGAGGAGCUGAGCCGGUAUGUGGAGGAACGGGACUUCAUCAUGCCGCUGGACUUAGGAGCCAAGGGCAGCUGCCACAUCGGGGGAAACGUGGCAACCAACGCUGGAGGCCUGCGGUUUCUUCGAUAUGGCUCACUGCAUGGGACUGUCCUGGGCCUGGAAGUGGUGCUGGCCGACGGCACUGUCCUGGACUGCCUGACCUCCCUGAGGAAGGACAACACGGGCUAUGACCUGAAGCAGCUGUUCAUCGGGUCGGAGGGCACUUUGGGGAUCAUCACCACGGUGUCCAUCUUGUGUCCACCCAAGCCCAGGGCUGUGAACGUGGCUUUCCUCGGCCUGCUUCACUCACAGCCACUUCUUCGGUUCUCCUGGGACCUGCCUGCGGCUCCUUUCUUGCUUCAUUUGAAUCGGGCGGGUUUAUCCAGCAUUUCCUCCUCAGGAGUUCAGAAGUCGCACAGCCCGGCAGUCUUCGCGCGGGAGGUGGCGGGUCUAGCUCACCAACUCCCAGUUCGGUGUCUUGAGCUGCCAGAAGCUUGGGCAGCCCUGGAGGAUGCUGAGACUCCGCAUGCUUGUUCCUUCAGCCACUUACAUCUUCUUGUUGUGAUGUGUGUUCCGUAUUUUAAGCAAUCUCACCAGGAUUAUUAUUUUAUGGCCACUUUCUCUGCCCUCCACUCUCUUGUGUCCGAUCUUCUGUCUGGGAUUAUGUUGCAAACAUAUCCUCGUUCAUUUCCUGCAGUAAAGGUCUCCUGGUGACCACUUCUUCACUUCUGGCGUGUCUGAAAAUACCUUUAUUUCAUCCUCAUUCUUGAAGGCUCUUUUCCACAGGCGCAUGGCUUCAGGCUGUUGUUUGUUUUCUUUUAUCCCGGUGGAAACGCUGACCCGCUGUCCUCUGGCCUCCUCGCUGUUGGGAACUUUGCUGUCGGUAGCUGCUGCUGUGAAGGGAUUCUGCCUCUCUCCUGGCCCCCCUUGGGCCACUUAAAGAUCAUUCUUUCUGAUCUUCUAAAGUUUUCAGUGUGUGGUGUGUGUGUGUACGUUCUUUUUCAUCUCCUUGGAAUUACUGAAUUUCUUAAACCUGUGGCUUGGUAUCUUUUACCAGUUCUAGAAAUUCUUAGCCAUUAUUGCUUCAGAUAUUGUCUGUGUUUUCCUCUCCUUUUGGGACUGUGAUUCAGGAUAGAAUGUCUCAGUCCGUCUUCUGUGUCUCUUAAUCUCCCCUCCAUAUUGUCAUCAUCGUGUCUCUCUGUGCUGCAUUCUGUGUGAUUUCUUCUCAUCUGUCUUCCAGUUCACGAAUGCCCUCUUCUGCUGUGUUUUAUUUGCUGCUGAACCCCUCCAUGAGUGGUUCCCUCCGUCCAUUGAGUUUUACAUUUUGAUUAUGAAAGUUUUUAUUUCUAAAAGUUUUGUUAUUUUUGUCAAAUCUGCAAUGUUACUUUUUAUAGUUUUCUAUUCUAGGUAUUCUCAAGCUCACCAUUUGUGUCUUUAAACAUAGUUUGACGUCUAUAAUCCCAGCACUUUGGGAGGCCAAGGCGGGUGGGUCAUUUGAGGUCAGGAGUUUGAGACCAGUCUGGCCAACAUGAUGAAACCCUGUCUCUACUAAAAGUACAAAAAUUAGGCUGGGCACAGUAGUUCACACCUGUAAUCCCAGCACUUUGGGAGGCUGAGGCAGGUGGAUCACGAGGUCAGGAGUUUGAGACCAGCCUGGUCAACAAGGUGAAACCCCAUCUCUACUAAAAAUACAAAAAUUAGCCGGGCAUGGUGGUGGACGCCUGUAAUCCCAGCUACUUGGGAGGCUGAGGCAGGAGAAUUGCUUCAGACCAUAAGGCAGAGGUUACAGUGGGCUGAGAUCAUGCCACUGCACUCCAGCCUGGGUGACAGAGCAAGACUCCAUCUCAAAAAAAAAAAAAAAAACUUUGAAUAAUUUUUUGUGAUGUUUUAUAAUCAGGCAAUUCCAUUUUUUCAAGUCUGUGUAGUCUGUGAAAGUUUUUUUUAGAGACAAGGUCUCACUCUGUUGCCCAAGCUGAAGUGCAGUGGUGUGAUCAUAGCCCCUGGGUUC